AUGGGCCACUCCUCCCAGCGGCAAGUGGAAAUCGAAGAUGUCAUGGGCUCCCACAGGCCACAGCCGGGCUCCCCACCCCCGGCACCCAGCUCUCUACGGCAGGUCCGGGAGGGCUGGGGCUUCGGGGAGCCCUACCCGCCAAACCUGCUGUUGGCCCGGGAGAGCCCCAGAGGCUCCCGGAGACUGCAGCCUCCUGUGCCACACUGUGGAAAAUACCUUUGCAGACGUGGCACCCGAGUGCACACACCGACCGCCACAUGUGCUUUUCUGCCGGGAAUCCCUGGGGUGAACGCAUGUUUUAUGGGCGUUUCCAGGAGCGCGCGUGCACCUCCAGACGGGGAGCUGGCGGGCGGGGGUGGCAGCAGCAGCUCUAGCCUUGGGGGGACAAGCCUCUCUCAGCUACGCCAGGGGAAAAGAGAGUUAAGGACACUCACCCCCACCCACGCACACACACAAGGCAGCGUCGGGUGGGAGAGAGAAGGCCGUUUCUCCUUCUGUAGCCUGGGUCUCCCACGGGCCUUCCCCGCUGCUGAGCGAGACACCAGUAGCCAGGUGAAGGGCCACAGCGGGCCAGGCCCCGACCCUGUUGUGACCCACCUGGGCACCUUCCCGGACCAGCUCCGCCUCCCCUGCCCUCCUCUCUCCAGGAAGGAGCCAGAACCCUCACCCCUCUCCCACCCUCCCCAGGGGUAA